GCCGUCCCCGCCGCCGCUGCCCGCCGCCACCGGCCGCCCGCCCGCCCGGCUCCUCCGGCCGCCUCCGCUGCGCUGCGCUGCGCUGCCUGCACCCAGGGCUCGGGAGGGGGCCGCGGAGGAGUCGCCCCCCGCGCCCGGCCCCCGCCCGCCGCGCCCGGGCCCGCGCCAUGGGGCUCUGGCUGUCGCCGCCCCCCGCGCCGCCGGGCUAGGGCGAUGCGGGCGCCCCCGGCGGGCGGCCCCGGCGGGCACCAUGAGCCCUCUGCUCCGCCGCCUGCUGCUCGCCGCACUCCUGCAGCUGGCCCCCGCCCAGGCCCCUGUCUCCCAGCCUGAUGCCCCUGGCCACCAGAGGAAAGUGGUGUCAUGGAUAGAUGUGUAUACUCGCGCUACCUGCCAGCCCCGGGAGGUGGUGGUGCCCUUGACUGUGGAGCUCAUGGGCACCGUGGCCAAACAGCUGGUGCCCAGCUGCGUGACUGUGCAGCGCUGUGGUGGCUGCUGCCCUGACGAUGGCCUGGAGUGUGUGCCCACUGGGCAGCACCAAGUCCGGAUGCAGAUCCUCAUGAUCCGGUACCCGAGCAGUCAGCUGGGGGAGAUGUCCCUGGAAGAACACAGCCAGUGUGAAUGCAGACCUAAAAAAAAGGACAGUGCUGUGAAGCCAGACAGGGCUGCCACUCCCCACCACCGUCCCCAGCCCCGUUCUGUUCCGGGCUGGGACUCUGCCCCCGGAGCACCCUCCCCAGCUGACAUCACCCAUCCCACUCCAGCCCCAGGCCCCUCUGCCCACGCUGCACCCAGCACCACCAGCGCCCUGACCCCCGGACCUGCCGCUGCCGCUGCCGACGCCGCAGCUUCCUCCGUUGCCAAGGGCGGGGCUUAGAGCUCAACCCAGACACCUGCAGGUGCCGGAAGCUGCGAAGGUGACACAUGGCUUUUCAGACUCAGCAGGGUGACUUGCCUCAGAGGCUAUAUCCCAGUGGGGGAACAAAGAGGAGCCUGGUAAAAAACAGCCAAGCCCCCAAGACCUCAGCCCAGGCAGAAGCUGCUCUAGGACCUGGGCCUCUCAGAGGGCUCUUCUGCCAUCCCUUGUCUCCCUGAGGCCAUCAUCAAACAGGACAGAGUUGGAAGAGGAGACUGGGAGGCAGCAAGAGGGGUCACAUACCAGCUCAGGGGAGAAUGGAGUACUGUCUCAGUUUCUAACCACUCUGUGCAAGUAAGCAUCUUACAACUGGCUCUUCCUCCCCUCACUAAGAAGACCCAAACCUCUGCAUAAUGGGAUUUGGGCUUUGGUACAAGAACUGUGACCCCCAACCCUGAUAAAAGAGAUGGAAGGAGCUGUCCCUGCCUGUGUCACUGUUUGUCACUGUCCAGGCUGGCUGGUUUGGGCAUGAAUGUCUGCAUCACUAAAUCCAGAGCUUGUCUUGCUCCCUCAUUGUGCAGAUGGAGGAAAUGAGGACUAAGGCCCCACAGCAGAUCCCAGGCAGGGCCAGAAUUAUGUAUUCAUCACUUUCAAGUUAUUGCCACGCAUGGGAGUCAGGGAUAGCCCAGUCAAUACAGACUGCCUGCCCUCCUGCUCUUCACCAGGGUUCUUUUCUAGAAGGAGACAGCCUUCUGUGGCCAGAGAGCUUGGGGUAGGACCCAGAUCUACUGAGUGACCUUGCUUGUCACUACCCCUGCCUCUCUGAGCAGCAGUUUCCACAUGUGCACAUAGAGGGAACAGAAGAUUGCUGUGGUUGGCGUCCUCGGGCCCCAGAGAAGUUUGAGACUAUCUUUACGUAAUAGAAAAGAACACUUGUUCUUCCUGCCAGGCA